CCCCGUCUCCUCCUCUUGCUCCCUCGGCCGGGCGGCGGUGACUGUGCACCGACGUCGGCGCGGGCUGCACCGCCGCGUCCGCCCGCCCGCCAGCAUGGCCACCACCGCCACCUGCACCCGUUUCACCGACGACUACCAGCUCUUCGAGGAGCUUGGCAAGUACGGCCCGCCCGCCGCGGUCCCCUGCCUGCCCUGCCGCCCGGGAGCUAUGCGGCUUCUCGCCCCGCCCCCCGGCCCUGCACCGGCCGCUGCGGCUCCCCCUCGGCCGCCCCACCCCCGCCUUUCCCGCCCGCCGCCUUCGGUCCCCGCGCCCCCCGCGCACUGCCCCGCAUCCCCCUCCGCGCCCUGCAGCAACUGGCGGGGCCGCUGCUCCCCACGCGCCGCCGCGGACACCGCAGACCCCGGACCGCUCCCGGGUGCCCUCCAGCCCCGCCCCUCCGCACCCUUCAGGCGCCCCCCUCCCGACCACCUCCCAACGCUGCCCGGUUGCUCACUCCGCACCCUGAACCCAGGUCCCACGCGCCUCGCACUCAGGACCCUCCCCAGCCCUGCAGCCCUAGCUCUGCUGCGGAGCCCGGGCGUGGGGGGGCUGUUUGGCGCCCGGCCCCGCCCCCCGCGGGUGCCGCUCCAGGCUCCCAGCCCCGCGGCUGGGCAGUGCUGCGGCACCCCCGUCCCCUCCCCCCACCCCUGCAGUGGUCCCGGGAGCCGCGCCGCAGCCUCAGCAUCCCCCUCCCCUCCGCACUGAGCUGGCCGCUGCAGCAGCCCCGGCCCCCCACCCCCACCCGCGGCGCCGAGCCCGGCCACUGCAGCCCCCGCCCCGCCCGCCCCCCCAGACGUUUCCAGAGCUCAGAGUGCGAGCUCCCGUUUGACGGGGACGUCAAGGAAAAUAGCAUGGGAAGGGGAGUUCUUGAUGUCUGACUGUGUCCUCUCUUCCCUUGCUGUCAGUUGAGCCGGGAUGCAGUGAGAUGAAACCGGCUGUGGGGGGGUUUGAGCCUCACUUUGCCCCAUGGUUGAGGGAGAUUUCUCUUUCAGGGGAUGAUACCCUCUUUUUAAUCUUUCCUUCCCCGACCUUCAACUGUUCCUGCUGAGAGAAGGGCAGGGUCUCUCUGCUCCCUUCUGCCCUGGUUCUCUUGGCCGGGACCGCAGGGCUGUCUGAGAUGCAGCAGGUGUGUGUUUUCAGCAUCGCCCACCCGCUCCUGAUGUGCAGCCUGAGGUGGAGGCUGUUGCCUUGCCCAGGGACUGGAUGAGGGGGUGGGAGCGCGGCACGCCACCCACAUCUGUUCAGUGUCCUGCGGUGGCCGCGUCCUUUUGCCUCAUGUUGGAUGGUGGUGGUCACAGCGCCGGUGUGUGUGCAUGGGUGCUUUCUCUGUGGUCCGCAGGUGUGUGAAGAAAACCUCCACGCAGGAGUACGCAGCAAAAAUCAUCAAUACCAAGAAGUUGUCUGCCCGGGAUCACCAGAAACUAGAACGUGAGGCUCGGAUAUGUCGACUUCUGAAACAUCCAAACAUCGUGCGCCUCCAUGACAGUAUUUCUGAAGAAGGGUUUCACUACCUCGUGUUUGACCUUGUUACCGGCGGGGAGCUGUUUGAAGACAUUGUGGCCAGAGAGUACUACAGUGAAGCAGAUGCCAGCCACUGUAUACAUCAGAUUCUGGAGAGUGUUAACCACAUCCACCAGCAUGACAUCGUCCACAGGGACCUGAAGCCUGAGAACCUGCUGCUGGCGAGUAAAUGCAAGGGUGCCGCCGUCAAGCUGGCUGAUUUUGGCCUAGCCAUCGAAGUACAGGGAGAGCAGCAGGCUUGGUUUGGUUUUGCUGGCACCCCAGGUUACUUGUCCCCUGAGGUCUUGAGGAAAGAUCCCUAUGGAAAACCUGUGGAUAUCUGGGCCUGCGGGGUCAUCCUGUAUAUCCUCCUGGUGGGCUAUCCUCCCUUCUGGGAUGAGGAUCAGCACAAGCUGUAUCAGCAGAUCAAGGCUGGAGCCUAUGAUUUCCCAUCACCAGAAUGGGACACGGUAACUCCUGAAGCCAAGAACUUGAUCAACCAGAUGCUGACCAUAAACCCAGCAAAGCGCAUCACGGCUGACCAGGCUCUCAAGCACCCGUGGGUCUGUCAACGAUCCACGGUGGCAUCCAUGAUGCAUCGUCAGGAGACUGUGGAGUGUUUGCGCAAGUUCAAUGCCCGGAGAAAACUGAAGGGUGCCAUCCUCACGACCAUGCUUGUCUCCAGGAACUUCUCAGUUGGCAGGCAGAGCUCCGCCCCCGCCUCGCCUGCCGCGAGCGCCGCCGGCCUGGCCGGGCAAGCUGCCAAAAGCCUAUUGAACAAGAAGUCGGAUGGCGGUGUCAAGAAAAGGAAGUCGAGUUCCAGCGUGCACCUAAUGCCACAGAGCAACAACAAAAACAGUCUCGUAAGCCCAGCCCAAGAGCCCGCGCCCUUGCAGACGGCCAUGGAGCCACAAACCACUGUGGUACACAACGCUACAGAUGGGAUCAAGGGCUCCACAGAGAGCUGCAACACCACCACAGAAGAUGAGGACCUCAAAGCUGCCCCGCUCCGCACUGGGAAUGGCAGCUCGGUGCCUGAAGGACGGAGCUCCCGGGACAGAACAGCCCCCUCUGCAGGCAUGCAGCCCCAGCCUUCUCUCUGCUCCUCAGCCAUGCGAAAACAGGAGAUCAUUAAGAUUACAGAACAGCUGAUUGAAGCCAUCAACAAUGGGGACUUUGAGGCCUACACGAAGAUUUGUGAUCCAGGCCUCACUUCCUUUGAGCCUGAGGCCCUUGGUAACCUCGUGGAGGGGAUGGAUUUCCAUAAGUUUUACUUUGAGAAUCUCCUGUCCAAGAACAGCAAGCCUAUCCAUACCACCAUCCUAAACCCACACGUCCACGUGAUUGGGGAGGACGCAGCGUGCAUCGCCUACAUCCGCCUCACCCAGUACAUCGACGGGCAGGGUCGGCCUCGCACCAGCCAGUCAGAAGAGACCCGGGUCUGGCACCGUCGGGAUGGCAAGUGGCUCAAUGUCCACUAUCACUGCUCAGGGGCCCCUGCCGCACCGCUGCAGUGAGCUCAGCCACAGGGGCUUUAGGAGAUUCCAGCCGGAGGUCCAACCUUCGCAGCCAGUGGCUCUGGAGGGCCUGAGUGACAGCGGCAGUCCUGUUUGUUUGAGGUUUAAAACAAUUCAAUUACAAAAGCGGCAGCAGCCAAUGCACGCCCCUGCAUGCAGCCCUCCCGCCCGCCCUUCGUGUCUGUCUCUGCUGUACCGAGGUGUUUUUUACAUUUAAGAAAAAAAAAAAAGAAAAAAAGAUUGUUUAAAAAAAAAAGGAAUCCAUACCAUGAUGCGUUUUAAAACCACCGACAGCCCUUGGGUUGGCAAGAAGGCAGGAGUAUGUAUGAGGUCCAUCCUGGCAUGAGCAGUGGCUCACCCACCGGCCUUGAAGAGGUGAGCUUGGCCUCUCUGGUCCCCAUGGACUUAGGGGGACCAGGCAAGAACUCUGACAGAGCUUUGGGGGCCGUGAUGUGAUUGCAGCUCCUGAGGUGGCCUGCUUACCCCAGGUCUAGGAAUGAACUUCUUUGGAACUUGCAUAGGCGCCUAGAAUGGGGCUGAUGAGAACAUCGUGACCAUCAGACCUACUUGGGAGAGAACGCAGAGCUCCCAGCCUGCUGUGGAGGCAGCUGAGAAGUGGUGGCCUCAGGACUGAGAGCCCGGACGUUGCUGUACUGUCUUGUUUAGUGUAGAAGGGAAGAGAAUUGGUGCUGCAGAAGUGUACCCGCCAUGAAGCCGAUGAGAAACCUCGUGUUAGUCUGACAUGCACUCACUCAUCCAUUUCUAUAGGAUGCACAAUGCAUGUGGGCCCUAAUAUUGAGGCCUUAUCCCUGCAGCUAGGAGGGGGAGGGGUUGUUGCUGCUUUGCUUCGUGUUUUCUUCUAACCUGGCAAGGAGAGAGCCAGGCCCUGGUCAGGGCUCCCGUGCCGCCUUUGGCGGUUCUGUUUCUGUGCUGAUCUGGACCAUCUUUGUCUUGCCUUUUCACGGUAGUGGUCCCCAUGCUGACCCUCAUCUGGGCCUGGGCCCUCUGCCAAGUGCCCCUGUGGGAUGGGAGGAGUGAGGCAGUGGGAGAAGAGGUGGUGGUCGUUUCUAUGCAUUCAGGCUGCCUUUGGGGCUGCCUCCCUUCUUAUUCUUCCUUGCUGCACGUCCAUCUCUUUUCCUGUCUUUGAGAUUGACCUGACUGCUCUGGCAAGAAGAAGAGGUGUCCUUACAGAGGCCUCUUUACUGACCAACUGAAGUAUAGACUUACUGCUGGACAAUCUGCAUGGGCAUCACCCCUCCCCGCAUGUAACCCAAAAGAGGUGUCCAGAGCCAAGGCUUCUACCUUCAUUGUCCCUCUCUGUGCUCAAGGAGUUCCAUUCCAGGAGGAAGAGAUCUAUACCCUAAGCAGAUAGCAAAGAAGAUAAUGGAGGAGCAAUUGGUCAUGGCCUUGGUUUCCCUCAAAACAACGCUGCAGAUUUAUCUGCACAAACAUCUCCACUUUUGGGGGAAAGGUGGGUAGAUUCCAGUUCCCUGGACUACCUUCAGGAGGCACGAGAGCUGGGAGAAGAGGCAAAGCUACAGGUUUACUUGGGAGCCAGCUGAGAAGAGAGCAGACUCACAGGUGCUGGUGCUUGGAUUUAGCCAGGCUCCUCCGAGCACCUCAUGCAUGUCCCAGCCCCUGGGCCCUAGCCCUUUCCUGCCCUGCAGUCUGCAGUGCCAGCACGCAAAUCCCUUCACCACAGGGUUUCGUUUUGCUGGCUUGAAGACAAAUGGUCUUAGAAUUCAUUGAGACCCAUAGCUUCAUAUGGCUGCUCCAGCCCCACUUCUUAGCAUUCUUACUCCUCUUCUGGGGCUAAUGUCAGCAUCUAUAGACAAUAGACUAUUAAAAAAUCACCUUUUAAACAAGAAACGGAAGGCAUUUGAUGCAGAAUUUUUGCAUGACAACAUAGAAAUAAUUUAAAAAUAGUGUUUGUUCUGAAUGUUGGUAGACCCUUCAUAGCUUUGUUACAAUGAAACCUUGAACUGAAAAUAUUUAAUAAAAUAACCUUUAAACAGUC